CUUGCUGGAUCAGAGGCUUUAAAAUCUUUUUUCAUCUUCUAGCUGUAGCUCGGGCUGCUUGUCGGCUUGGCCUCCCCCUCCCCCCUUUGCUCUCUGCCUCGUCUUUCCCCAGGACUUCGCUAUUUUGCUUUUUUAAAAAAAGGCAAGAAAGAACUAAACUCCCCCCUCCCUCUCCUCCAGUCGGGCUGCACCUCUGCCUUGCACUUUGCACAGAGGUAGAGAGCGCGCGAGGGAGAGAGAGGAAAGAAAAAAAAUAAUAAAGAGAGCCAAGCAGAAGAGGAGGCGAGAAGCAUGAAGUGUUAACUCCCCCGUGCCAAGGCCCGCGCCGCCCGGACAGACGCCCGCCGCGCCUCCAGCCCCGAGCGGACGCCGCGCGCGCCCUGCCUGCAGCCCGGGCCGGCGAGGCGAGCCCUUCCUUAUGCAAAGCGCGCAGCGGAGCGGCGAGCGGGGGACGCCGCGCACCGGGCCGGGCUCCUCCAGCUUCGCCGCCGCAGCCACCACCGCCGCCACCGCAGCUCGCGGAGGAUCUUCCCGAGCCUGAAGCCGCCGGCUCGGCGCGCAAGGAGGCGAGCGAGCAAGGAGGGGCCGGGGCGAGCGAGGGAGCACAUUGGCGUGAGCAGGGGGGAGGGAGGGCGGGCGCGGGGGGCGCGGGCAGGGCGGGGGGGUGUGUGUGUGAGCGCGCUCGGAGGUUUCGGGCCAGCCACCGCCGCGCAAGCUAGAAGCGCCCCAGCCCGGCAAGCUGGCUCACCCGCUGGCCACCCAGCACAGCCCGCUGGCCCCUCUCCUGCAGCCCAUCUGGCGGAGCGGCGGCGGCGGCGGCGGCGGCGGCAGGAGAAUGGCAUCAGAACUGGCAAUGAGCAACUCCGACCUGCCCACCAGUCCCCUGGCCAUGGAAUAUGUUAAUGACUUCGAUCUGAUGAAGUUUGAAGUGAAAAAGGAACCGGUGGAGACCGACCGCAUCAUCAGCCAGUGCGGCCGUCUCAUCGCCGGGGGCUCGCUGUCCUCCACCCCCAUGAGCACGCCGUGCAGCUCGGUGCCCCCUUCCCCCAGCUUCUCGGCGCCCAGCCCGGGCUCGGGCAGCGAGCAGAAGGCGCACCUGGAAGACUACUACUGGAUGACCGGCUACCCGCAGCAGCUGAACCCCGAGGCGCUGGGCUUCAGCCCCGAGGACGCGGUCGAGGCGCUCAUCAGCAACAGCCACCAGCUCCAGGGCGGCUUCGAUGGCUACGCGCGCGGGGCGCAGCAGCUGGCCGCGGCGGCCGGGGCCGGUGCCGGCGCCUCCUUGGGCGGCAGCGGCGAGGAGAUGGGCCCCGCCGCCGCCGUGGUGUCCGCCGUGAUCGCCGCGGCCGCCGCGCAGAGCGGCGCGGGCCCGCACUACCACCACCACCACCACCACGCCGCCGGCCACCACCACCACCCGACGGCCGGCGCGCCCGGCGCCGCGGGCAGCGCGGCCGCCUCGGCCGGUGGCGCUGGGGGCGCGGGCGGCGGUGGCCCGGCCAGCGCUGGGGGCGGCGGCGGCGGCGGCGGCGGCGGAGGCGGCGGGGGCGCGGCGGGGGCGGGGGGCGCCCUGCACCCGCACCACGCCGCCGGCGGCCUGCACUUCGACGACCGCUUCUCCGACGAGCAGCUGGUGACCAUGUCUGUGCGCGAGCUGAACCGGCAGCUGCGCGGGGUCAGCAAGGAGGAGGUGAUCCGGCUGAAGCAGAAGAGGCGGACCCUGAAAAACCGCGGCUAUGCCCAGUCCUGCCGCUUCAAGAGGGUGCAGCAGAGACACGUCCUGGAGUCGGAGAAGAACCAGCUGCUGCAGCAAGUCGACCACCUCAAGCAGGAGAUCUCCAGGCUGGUGCGCGAGAGGGACGCGUACAAGGAGAAAUACGAGAAGUUGGUGAGCAGCGGCUUCCGAGAAAACGGCUCGAGCAGCGACAACCCGUCCUCUCCCGAGUUUUUCAUGUACCCAAGGGAAUCCUCUACAUCAGUGAUGUGAAAAAAUCCAGUUGCCUGAAGUCAAAGAGAAAAUAUGCUGGCAUGCUAAUCGCGUGAGACAACUUGGCCCACGGACAGCCACAAAGCACAAAAACAAAACACAAACUCACUCAGAGAAGAAACAAGAAUCGUGUUUUCCUGGCAUCUACGAGAAGCGCUUUAUUAGAAGCGCUUUAUUUUUCCUCUAGAUUUCUUUUCUAAAAAAUGAAAAACAAAAACAAACUGAAACAAACAUUUAAAGAAACAAUACAAACUUCAGGUGAUGAUAUUCAAGCAUGUUCUUUUAUUAAGCAUAGGAUGCGAGGCACAGCAGGAGGUUUAAGUACAAUGUGAAAGCAAGAGAACUGAGACUGUGAUUGACAGACAAAGGGAUUAACUAACGUUUUAUUCUCUGCCCCCCAAAAUAUCCUGUGUAUUCUUAAGUAUAUACGCUUCCCUUCCUGCCUUUCAAGGUAUCUAAGGAAUGAUUUGAAAAAUUUGUUAUAAUCUCUAAAGAAUUUUUUGCAUAGCAUUAGCAAAGGAGUCUAUGACAAGUACUUUGCCACCUGGUAGUUCUGCGUAUUCUACUCCCUCUGGGUGUCACUGUCAUCCUCACUGGCUGGGACAAGGUUCUGAGAUUUGUCUCCCCAGCAGUUGCUAAGCUGGCUCAGUCUUGGUCAGGAUGAAUGAAACAAUUAUCUCCUGGAUCAAUGCAGCAAGGAGCAGUGAACACUUGCUUUUUCUUCCCUAAGUAGGAGAAGGCCAGCCCCCGGCUGCAGUGGUGGCCGUGGUGGUAGCUGGAUGGGACGAGGGGACCUCAGGCUAUUCUAUAACAGUAAAAGAAAGAGAAUUGCUGGUGCUUCUCCAGGGAGAUACGGAACCUACACACCAAGCAGGUUUUUACUUUCAAACAGGCCACCACCAGAAAGCAAAGAGACCUAUGCCUAGCCCAGCCCCAGAAAAGUGAUACUUUACCCCAGGAAUUCCCUGCUUCCCAUUGGUACUUAAGAUUUUUCACUCUGUUGUGACUGCUCUUAUUUCCUUUACUCUUGCGGAUCUGUGUUGGAGGGACAUUUGGAAGGGGCCCAGCCCUGGCACUUGCGUGAGGGGACACACACAGGGCGGGUGUGUGUGCCCAUCCGCUCUGAGCUCCACUUAGCCGGACUGGCUGCCAAGCCGUUCUUGGAUCAGCCUCUCGCUGAGCGCCCACAGGGUCCGGGCCGUCUCUUCGCUCUGAGCUUCUGGUGAGGGCAUGCAGCGGCAGCAGUUGUUGAAGUACAUCCCUCCCAGACCCUCCAGUUCUGGGACAGCAGCACAGUACACGGUGGUGGCAGCUCCCUGUUGCUGGAAAUCCAAGAAGAAAGACAAAAAAAAAUUUUAAGAAAAGGAGUGAUGAGAUGGCGUCAUUUCGACUGCCUGGGCAUUAGCAGGCCUCCCCCACCUGGUUCAGUUUCAGCUGGAUCUUGGCAUAGCAAAGGGUACUGGGCUGAAAGCACAUGACUGUAAAAAGUAUAAUGUGACUAUCCUGGAAAAACGAGUUCAUAAACUCCGCUUGUAAAGCUGGUGUAACUUUUGACACCUCAUACAGGGACAGGCUUGGAAAAUAAAUACACAUAUCAAUACGUCGUGGCAGGCGCCUCUUCCACACAGAGAAAAAGAUGGUAUCCUUCUGAACGUGCAAGAACAAAUUCAUCCAACCCCUCAACUUCUCCAUGUAUAAUGUAAUUCGAUACCAAAUCGUUUGUAGAACCUUCUGUCUGACAAACCAACCACUCUUAAUUGUGGUCCAUCAGGUAGAAAACCCAAGUGGGGCUGCUGCCAGAUCAUCCCUUUAUGCUUUGCCCACGGUGCUGCUAGGGGAAGGGUUGGCAAUGUUGUGUUAAAACAUUUAAUGCACACACACACACACACACACACUCCUCACCAUACAUUCAUACUUAGCACAAACACAUAACACAUUAAUUCAUCCAGAUCCCAUGAAAACCUUUUUCUAAAUGUCAUAUUUGACCCAGAUUUACAAUGGGACCACAGGUAAGGGGGUACAUUUCCUCCCAGCCCACUUCAAAAUGUAAGUUGCAAAGAGUGCAGCUGAUCACUUUCAUUCACCUUUUGAGUAACAGUUGCGGCUGUGGCUAGGGACGUGUGCAGUGAUGAGGCAUCAUAUCAUCCAAACUGACAGAAUACUGUCAGGGAUGCUAUAAAGAGGGCAAGAAAUCACUUUGCUUUGCAAGCCAUAAUUAAAAAUAAUAGGCUGCUGUUCAGAGGGAGACAUGGUCGGCACGUCUCUAAUUUAAAACCAAUACAGUUUAUCUGGCAUCUUAUGAUUAUUUAUGUGUUUCAGAGCCCUAGCUGCAUCCACUAAUUUUCAGCUGAUGAGAGGGAGAGGGGUUGCAAGAGAGGACCGGAAAAGGUAACUGAAGAUAAGCUCGCCCCCACAAGGAAAACACUAAGGAACUUUGAUUGUGGGGGAAAUGGCUUUCCGACCCGACCCAAAGCUUAUCAUUUUUCUGCCCCUGCAGGGUUUACAUUGUGACCAUGCAGGGUGCUUACUGGAGGAGUUUCCCUCAAAUGGUCUGGUUUGCAAUCACUAUGCUUGCAUUCUAGGAUCCCUGGGAGAGUCAGGUCCAUACUGAGAAAUAGGGUCCCAAGGAAGGUGUUACGACGUGAAGAAUCUGCCAUAAGGCAGACUUGGGUUUGUUGUUGUCAUUGUUGUUUGGUUUUAGCUUCUUCAGUGUCAGGAUAUCUAGUAACAAUGGAGUUGGUCUGAAAACUGAAUGGUCAAAUGCAGUCAAGUGAUACGACUCUGGGCGGGGUGUGGACCGUGAGUGAGACAAAGACUUGGGUUUUGAUAAUAACUGGCUGCUUGAUGAUACUGGACAAGUUCCACUGGUCCUGAAUUUGAAUAACUGACAUGACUUGAACUUAAUAGUAGCUGGUUUGUUACCUCCCCAAUCUCCCUCCAUUAUCAUGCCCACUCCAAAUAGCCAGAUAUUAUCCUGGAUUCAGCUGUUUCUUUUCCCAUUGAUUUGUGUGGCUCAAGUCUAAUGGAAAUGAGUUCAUGUCAUCCAAAUUUCCUUUCACUGAAUUAUUAUUCCUAAUAACCCUGAGCUUAGCACCUGGCACAUUUAUCUAAACAACUUCAAGGGGUUUAUCUGGCUCUUCUGCAUCCCAUGUGGGGAAAAGGGAAGCAGAAGUGCCUCUAAAGACAAAUUGGAGAAUUGAGAUGCUCAUCCAGCUAACUCAAGCCAAGUAUUAUUUUGGCCUGGAAUCUUAGAGUUCUGGUGGAGAUGGUGUUUUGUAUCAACUUCCAGAUAUCUGUCAUAUAUUUUCAUUUUACCUUGCAGCUGCCAAAACGACCAGAGUGGCCAAGUGACUUGCCAUUAACUCCCGAGUGGUGGGAGAAUCCAGCUCACCCAUUUCAAGUCCAGCCUCCCGCCCUCUAUGCCACAAUGGUUAUACUAUUCAGCAUUCAAACGUCAUGACAGACUGGCCUUUCACUGUUCUGCCAAGCGUGAGGAAAGACCAAAGCAGUCCGUUUGGGAAAGCAAAAAGCAGAAUUCUUCCUAACCUGAUAAAAUAUUUUGCCACUAUGACCUACUGUAAUGAUACCACGUUGCACUCUUGCAUUACUGGAAUGGUAUUUUUGCUAAGAAAUUCUGCAGUCCCAUUGAUUCAGAAUGCCAUUGUUGCAGGAGCUGGGGACCUACCUUUUCCUUCCACGGAAUCUAAAGGCAAUUACAACUGGCUUCAUUUCAUGCCAACCUACAUUUGGCUACAAUGCUGAGAGCCAUACCUUUUUGAAAAGCCUAACUUUUUAUCAGGAGAUGGCUUUGAUUCCUUUGCCACUAGGCUUGGGGUGAUUUACCAUCUAAAUUCCAUCACAAGUGGCUCUGGCUUUGUAGAACACAGUACACAGGAGGGGCACCCGAAAGCAAAGACGACCUUCUCUACUCCAAAAAUCAAUCGUCCACCUUUGGCAAAUUCUCCUUCUCAGAUUCAUGCUUGGUGCUCAUGGGUACUCACUCUACUUUCCUCCCUUGCUGGACAAUUAAGCAGUAACAAUAUCUUGUUGGUCCCAUACACACCACACCUUUGGUCUCUUGGAGAAUUUUCAGCCGUACCAAUGGCAACCUCUGAGUGACAUCUUAAUAUGAUCAGAUGUGAUGACAGUUUAGUAACAGGUUCUCAUUUUUGGCUCACCAGCUUUUCGGCCUACAUAUCAUCAGAAUAAGACUGAGGCACAUUAGUGAAAUCUCAAUAGUAAACAAGCAGGUACUGCCAAUAAAAGAGAAAGCAUUCUUAAACUGAUUAAAAAAAAAAUUUAAAGAGCACUUUAAUCACCAUCAGAUGACUUUCAUUCAUACCACCUUUUGGGGCAUCAGUUCAUAAUGCAGAAAAGAUGAAAGAGCCAUCUAAAGGAAAUAAUGUUAACAACUCCGUUAUAAAAUAUCUGAAGCAAUACCUUGCCAGUUGUCAUCAAUGCUUACUGAUCCAUUGUGAUAAAUAAUAAUACCUUGACAUACAAACACUGGCUGGAGCUAUGGGUUCCCCUAAACGAUUUUUUUUUUUUGAGAAUCAAUCAUUUAUCAGAAGCCUGUAGGUUGUAUAUGGUUGCUAAUCAUGGGAAACGGGGGAGGUGUCUAUCCCGCAGCAAUGGCAAUGAGUUAGGUUGUUGACGACACAGGACUGAGAAUUUCUGGGAAGCCCAGAAGAAUCUUUUUAAUCAUGCCCGAAUGCCAUUUCCGAUCUAGUCAAACAUUUGUGAGCUGCCAGAGGAGAACUGUGCAAUCAAUCUUGAGAGUAUAUGUAAAAUUACCCAGGACUCUUGUUUGGGAUUAAGAGUAUCUUGGUAAUAAGGAUUCAUCAUUCUCUUUCAAAAAUCAUCUGUCAGAUUUGCAGCACAAUCUUCAACUACAGAAAGGUGGGAUUUAGAAAGCAGUUGCUGUUUAUUUAUAGUUGAGGCCCUCAGAUCUAAAUUAUCCAUCCUUCCAAAACUCGGUGUUGGGAUGAAAAUGUUAAGUAGCUGCUUUUCAUCAACAUUCAUUUGAUAACUGCUAGCCAUCAAUUUAUAGUUGUCAGCACAGAAUACAAAUGCAUAUUGACUCCUUUAAAGGAAAGGGUACAGAGGUUUCUGAUAAACAAUAUAUGGUAAAGAAAAAAAAAGCACCCACAUAUUGAUAUUUGUAAUGCAUUGGUUAGUACUCUAAUAUAAUACUCACAGGGACACAUGUUACACCGUGUUUUGCUUUCAGGUUUUUCUAUUUUAAAAUGCAUGCUCAUUUAAAAGAAAGAGGAGAUUCCUGUCUUAAAGUAGACUUAACUAUGAGAUAUAUAAAAAAUAGACACAAUAUCAUGGCAUAUCUAUAUAUUCAAUGAUUGUGAGAGAGUAGAUGUUCUAAGAUUGCUUUCUUACAGGGACAUUGCACAGCAAAUGCUGAAUUAAUCCACUUAUGCAAAAAGUAGAGUUAUGAAAGGAAUGAACCCUGGAAGUUAGAUUAGGCUUGGAACACCAAGAGCAGGGAAGGAGAACAGCCCUUUUGAAGACGGCAGUGUUCCCAUGACUAACGUCCCAGGACAAAGUGGUGAUCUGAAGUGAGCAGGUUUGGCUAAAAGGAAAGACACAUACCUCUUCAAACCCUGCCUACUUCCAUUGUUACUCAUCUGGUGUCUGUUGGACAAAGCAAAUACUUCUCAAAUGCAAAGCCAGCCACCUUAUCCAUUGACUCUGUGAAUACACCACUAGGAACAGAAUCAUUUAUCAGAGAGCUACAUUUAUCAGAGAGCUGCUGCGGUGGAGAUGAGGGGGUGAGCCCUCAUGUCACAGGUGGAAUAGAUGGCCGUCUACACGCCCUGUCUUUCCCUGUCUCCCAGUAACACUCCCCCAGGAGAGGCUAUAACCACUCUCCCAGAACAGUGCAGAGGUCAUCUCCAGAUACCUCGGUGCUUGGGAUACAGCCAUUCCUCACAAACAAUUACAGCUUCAAUCUCUCAUUGGAAACACAAAUGAAAGCAAACUGCUCCAAAAGGCCACUUGUUCCCUACUCACUAUCCAAGAGCAAUCUUUUAGGGGACACAUUUGCCACAAAUUGCAUUUGUUCAUAAAGUAAUGCAGCCUAUACAGGAAUGAGGCUCAUAGGCCUCCCUGGCUAGGUGACCACACCAGUAAGUCACCCUCUUCUUCCACCGUGAUACUUCUAUAAUGAAAUUAUACAAUUCAAUUUGGAAUAAGUGCUAACCAACGAACACACCAACUUCCACCAAAAUGAUGGGAAGCAGCAGACGAGAACAGAGAUGUCUACUCCAAAGUCCUCAGCCCUGCAAACUGCCCGGCUUUUUCAGUGAGUUGUAGCCAACGAGUACUAUUCAAGUGACAUCAAUGACUAGCAUUUAUUGAGAGGUUACGAUUUGCCAGGCUCUGCAUGGAGAGCUUUGUAAGCAUUGUUGCCUAACCCUCACAGAGCUCUAUGAGCCAGGGACAGUUAGUAUUUCCAUUUAUUUAGAGAGAAGCCUACCUGAUAUCAGAGAUCAAAAGCAACUCGUCCAAAGCCAUACAGAUAAUUACGUAGAGUGAGUGACUUCAGACUCCGUGUCCGUUGGUACAUGAAACCUGCUCCCCAAAUAUGUGACACAAAUAUUUGCACGUGGCCCAUUUCCUCAUCUAUGUCUUCCACGGGGCUCCGGCUUCCUAUGCCUCUCUGCCUGCUCUGCCGCCUUCUCAGCCAGGCCAUGUCUGGCCAUGAGGUGAUGCCCUAACAUGGCCUAAAAUGAAAUGUGGGGGCUGUCGUGUGUUCACCCGAGAAAUGUUAAAAGGAGAUUUUUUUUUCCAUUGAUUUACUCAUGGAGCUAAAUUGAAAUGAUAUCCAUUUGGAUGAACAAAAAUGAAGACUCAGCACCCCCUUCGAUGAUCCAACAGCAAGUGACCCUUACUAAAAAGGUCGUCCGAUUCAAAAUGCCAUCUCCAGGUGCCAGAUUUGCAGAACUAAGAAACCUACUCUUUGAUGAUAGAAUUUUUUCAAAGCACCGACAUCCCAUACAAGUGAAGUGGACACAACCCCCAUCUUAUCAGUUCCCACGCAUGUAGGUGCGGGCUCUGGAGUGUUUCAUCAGGUUUGCAGAGAAAAUACUGAUCCAUCCCUCUGACUCCCUCUCCUCCAAUGAUUCCUAACACAGUCAUUCCUACAAAUUCCUGACAACUGACUCCCACAAAGGCCUUCAACAAUCCAGCCUUAGACACAUGCAAAUACUUCCUGUAGGUAUUGAAAUGUAACUUUCUUCAUAAACCUUUGGGAGUUUUGCUAACUCACAGGCUAUUCUUAACCUUUAUUAUAGAAGAGGAAUGCACUCAAUUUCCCAAAAAGAAACAAUGAAGAUGAUCAGGAAAGCAAAUAUUUGUUUUCAGGCUUUAGAAGUGUGAGAAAGUGUUCUGGAGAAUCCAUUUAGAUCCCAUGCCAACUCUUAGCCCUCCAGAAGAGAACAUGCCCUCCCUAACAAAUUAGACGUGGACAAUGUGUUUAGAUGUUGAUCUUUUGCCACAAGGAAAAAUAUUUCUUUGCUAGCAACAGGUUCACAAAGGUAGAAAAACCUCAGGCUCCUUUUCAGUUGCCUCUCCCAUGACAGGUGAAGAGUGUCAUUCCCCAGGUGACACUAGGGACAGUGUCUAUGACAGGGGCUUGAUGGCCGUGGCUCAGAGAGAGUAAAGUGCCAGUCCAUCACCAUAAAUGCAACAGGUUCAAGCACAGACCACAACCACAAAUUACAAGGGACACCUUGAGAGAAACGCAUGCAGGGGGAAGAGUGCCAUGCAGCUUUUAAAUGACAGGCACGUGCUCACAGGCUUCUGUUCAGAGAGAACCUGUGAGCUGUCCUGUGGCCUUUCCUGUUUACGGUGCAGCCAUCCCAAAUAUGAUGCCCCCAAAUCCGAGUCUGGCUAGAAGGAAGUGUCAUACAAAGGCCAUGCCAUUCUCCCUGACAAAAGACAUGAGUUUCUUGCAAGAGCACUAAGAAGUUUUAAGAGGUGGACUCGAAGAGAGGAGAAUGAAUUGGAAAGCCAGCAAGAAUGUGGCUCUUACUCCUCUGUGAAAUAUUUGCAGGAACGAGCCUGGAGACCAGCAGGUUCAGGAUGGAAAGCUGGAAAGAAUUCUUUCCUAAAACUUAAGUUUUAGAGAAAAAUAGGCAGCCAGUCCCAACCACCCAAAGGCGUCCAAAGCCAUGUUUGUUCUGGGAAGGCCAAGGCAUGGGAGGAUGUUAACUUGGGCUAUCAGCAGGAUUGAAGGGCAGGGUGACCUUGGUACGCUCUCAGGGCCUGUGUUUCCAAGUCGACAAACUGUUCUGAGCUUUUCCAUGAAACGAGUGAAGCCCUUUUCAUACCUCCUUCGUGUUCCAGAAUUCUUGCCAUCGAUGUUCCAAAGGAUCUGUGAUAGAUUUAUGUCUAGCCUUAAAUGGGACGAGUUGUAACAUUCAGAAUUAUUUUAUCUUUCUGAGACCUGCUAUUAUUGUGAGACCCUAGACAUGCUUUGCUGGGGUUAGGGUGAGGGUACUCCUAACGAGGGAAGGAAAAAGAAACGGCUUCAAGGCAAUCCAUGUGGGUCAUUACAUGCACACUUGUUCCAUCUUCCAUUUGUGCCUGCCCAAAGCGUUCUAGAACUGACCGGACCUGAGAGGCUGUCUCAUUAGAACUAAGAGAAGGUAUUGUUGAUGAUGUCUUAUAUCCAUGGAAGAAUUCCCUGGGCAUUCCCUCUGAUGCUGCCUGGGAUACCUACAUUGCUCAAAGUACAGUUUCUUUAUGAAUAGGGAUGAAACAUCGCAUUGGGGUAUCUAUUCUUCCAUGGUUGGUUUGAAAUAGCCAAGCAGAAGUGCCAUAGAAAUUUGCCAACAAAAUAAGCAUCUAACUGAUAGUGUCGUCCUUCUACAUGGAACAAAUCUGAUGGCAUGUCACUGAAAUUUUCCAACUGGGCCACCUUGAUGCCCGUGCUAAAGGACUGCUGGGUGUUUAUAAGAUAUAAAAGAAGAUAUUUAGUGUGUGUUUAUUUGAAACAUUUUACAUUUUUACUCUACUUCUUUAACCUCUGUUAUGGUUAUAGCUAGCUCGUGUACUGCGUAUAAAUGUAUGCAUCUGUAUUCGCCAUCUACACCAAAAUAAACCUUUGAAAUUAUUGCCAGGCAGAAUUAAUGAGCUCAGUUCUAACAGCGCAAAGAAUAUCUUCAUACUACAGGUAAAACAAACAGCUUCUCCCUUCCCUUCUUCUGCACAGAAUGGCUCUACGAAGUCUGCCUGCAAAAUUACGUCUUUUAGAAAACCAAGUAGCUGGCUGUUUUGUGAGCAGGGAGGAUUUCAGGACGAACCACAAACAAGCUGUUUGUUUAGAUUUUAAGGUUGACAGUUCAUUUACACGUAUGCCCCAUAAGUAUUCUAUAACAUAGUCCUGAAAAAGCACUGAAGAAAAAAAAAAAAAAAAACACAAGGUCUCCGCUGGGGCCACAUCAUGGGAAGGAAUUAACUCUUAACUCUGCCUUCCAGAAACAAAUUAAGAGGAUGUACUUUGCAAUAAUUCAGAUCUCACAGGUAGGCCCCCAAUGUCCAGCCCCGCUAUUUCAAAUCGGGCAUGUCUGAGUUAGGUGUGUGGAUUUCCAUACAGAGCUCACUGGAACAGACCAUUUCUCAGGUUCCAAGACGCUGGCCUUGUUAAUAUUUCAUUUAGAACAUACUGUGGAGAGUGUCUCAUUUAUAUUACUUCCAUAAUUAAUGGUGAUAGCUUAGGCACUGCCUUUACACAGAGAGAUCUCUUCACAGUGGUCGAUGGGUAAUGAGAAACAAUAGAUAUUUCAUUCACCAGCAGCGUGUUGCUAGUUAGUAGGAAAUGAUCGUGUGUGCUGUUGCUUUAAUUGCCCGGGUAAAUAAUUCUGCCUCGGUGUUAGUGAGCAUUUUAAAGCACUUGAUGCCAAUAGACUAGAAACAAACAAAAAUUAACCUUGAUUAUGCAACACCUUAGCAUAGAAAGUUACAAAGGUAUGUCUUUUUUAAAGUUUGCAUUCUAUCAUGCAAAUAUUAUCUAAAUAUGCAUGUGCUGACUACUCAUCUACUGUAUUUUAGGAAAUACAAUUAGGCUGCCUUUCUCUUCCCCUAUGUAGACUGUAAAUAACUGUAGAUCUUUCUCUUGUUUCCCUAUGUAAAUAUAUGUAAAUACUAACAAGCUAUGCAUGCUGCUAUUCUAGGCAAUUUCAGGUACUUUUAUAAUAUGAAGGCAUGUACUUGAACUCGUUUGUUAACAGAGGGGAAAAAACUCUCUCAAACUCUUUAAAGCUGAAUAGAAAUUAAAGAUUUCUUCCUAGA